AAGCUUAUUCCCAAUGUCCUUUUUCUAUUCCAGUAUCCGAGAGGACACCAUAUUGCAUUUAGUUGUCAGGUCUUAGACUCUUCUUGGCUGUGGUGGUUGCUCAGACUUUCCUUGUUUUGAUGACCUUGGCAGUUUUGGGGAGUGCUGGGCUGGUGUUUUGCAGGUUGCCCCUCUACUGGAGUUUUUCUGUACUGGAGUUUUUCUGUACUGGAGUUUUUCUCUACUGGAGUUUUUCUCUACUGGAAUUUUUCUGUACUGGAGUUUUUCUCUACUGGUGUUUUUCUCUACUGGUGUUUUUCUCAUGAUUAGACUGGAGUUACAGGUUUUGGGGCAGAAACCACAGAAGUGAAGUGCCUUCUGCUCCCAUCUUUUGAUGUACACAGUAGCUACCUGGCUUAUCACUGUCUUGACUUCGAUCACCUGGCCAACGUAGUGGGUGCCAGGUUGCUCCAAGGUGAAGUUAUUCGUUUCCUUCCCUCCCCCUUCCAUAUAUUAACAUGAACGCAUUUGUAUGCAUGCAUAGAUGCUGUAUGUGGAGUGUGCUGUACUCUCCAGAAGGCAGGAAGUCGCUGUGUGCAGCCCACACUUAGGGGUAUGGUGGUGUACACCACCACCAUGAGAGUGGAGGAUCUAUGUAAAUUGUUUGGAAUUUUUCUGCAUAGGAGAUUUGUCUUGUUUCCCAUUUAUUUUCAUCAGUAUGGAUUCCCGGGAAGAUGAACUCCCAGUGUUGUACUUGGGUGUGAUUCAGGAGUAUGCAAGCCUUUCUGCCCCACUUUGUUGCCUUGUUAACUAAGGGAGGCUGAGAUAAGUCCUCUCAGGUGCAGUCAGAGUCUGUCCUAAGAUGGGGGUAGGGAGUUGCUGUGCCUCAGUGGUUUACUUUCUCAAUAUAGACUGUUAGCCAUAUGUGUGUUACCUGAAACCUUAAGGAGAAAGCAUUUUUGGCCGGCCUGGAAAGGACACAAGCAAAUGUAGCCUUGAUGGUGGAGAAACGUCUCUAGCAGGGCUGUGCAUCUGAAUCAGCAUUGAAGCAGCGCCACCUUGUGGUUGAUGCUGAAUGAGCUGUGUAUUCGGCCAGGUUCUGUGAUUCUUACCCUGUCUGCAUGCUGUUCGAGUAGCUAAAGUACUUUAGAAAAGAAGAAACACUUUAAACUCUUAAAGAAAAAGAGAAGCUACCUCCUAACUUUGCCUUUGUACAUGACUGGGUACACAAACAGCAGACAUCUUAAAGUAAAAAAUCUCUGUAGUUACUUUGUUUGACAUACUGUUAAUCAUGUAUUUUCUGGUAAGCCUUUUUGUCUCUGAUUGUUCAAAAUUGUUCAAUAGCUGAGGCGUAAAAGUAGAAUAGGUUAUAACCCCAAGCCUCUGUCAUAUUUUUCUUUGGUAUAGGCAGAUUGGGCAGUUAUUUUAAUAUUCAUUCUUCUUUGCCCCCAAAUGUCUUCAGAUGUUUUUGUACACAUGCGUAAGAGGUUUGAGCCUAUGUAGGAAGUAGCCAGGGAGUCUACUGAAGUCCACUGUAAUGUGUGGGAAUGUGGAGCCAGUUAUGAUUAACAGCUGUCUGCAUCCUGGAUUGUUUAACCCAUUGUUUACACCCACUCUUCAGAACCAGUGGAGGUGGGGGAGUUGGGAAGAUGGUUUCAUAUGACCUGUGGUUGACCUGAUUGACUGUUAGCAGGUGCUAAGAUGGAGAUCAGUUUCAGUUGGUUUUAAAAAAAAUCAAGAAGCAGCCACUCUGUUGUAAUAAAUCAUUGUAUAUUCAGGAAUUCUAACUGUAAUGUAAAAUCUUGAUCACCUGUUUUAGAGUAAGGUAAGCAAUGACUGUAGUUGCUUUAACCAAUAAAAAUUCGACAUCAACCUGAGCUGUAGCAUGUUUAAUGUGGAAACCCUGUUCUCUGUUUUGUCCUGAAUGCUGAACACUGAUAGGAAGUCAGAUGCGGUAGCUGAGAGGUCACGAUGGCCUGGGUUGCUGCAGGGGACGGCAGCAGGCACUCUUAGGAGGUGAGCUGCGGUCGUGGCUUAUCUGGCCCCUCUCACUGAUGUCACAGGUUACCUAUGCAAUCUGUGAGUGCAAUUUGUCCUUUUUAGACUCUAAACAGAUAAUGGCUGAGCCCCCAAAUAUGGCUUUGCUGCUGCGCUUGAUGUUUGCAAGAGGGAAGAGGUGUUUCAGAUAAUGGAAAGCAUGUGCUUGCCAGUGUGAGCUCAUCAACAAUGAGGUCAGAGGAGGACAGUGCCUCUUGCUCGCAAGCCCAGCCUUCAUACUGCCUUUUCUUUCAGUCUCAGGUGCAGCCUGUUGUGGGAUUGUUAGAGGCCCCUUGCAUGUGGUCUGACAUGCCAGCCUUCUGACCAUGUGCAACAGGACUGUGGGCUACUCCUGACUUCAGAGAUAGCAUCUUUGUACAGAUGCCAGAGAUGCCAGAGACACCCAGGAGUUGAGUCUGCUGGGGGACAUGGACAAGGACGUCCCGUCAGGAAGCCCAAGUAUGUGGAAAGCCCCAGAGUGCCUGGAGAUGCAGUUAUAAUGCCAUUCAGAGAAGUAGCCAAGCCAACAGAGCCUGAUGAGCAUGAAGCAAAGGCCGAUAAUGAACCGAGCUGUUCGCCGGCAGCUCAAGAACUGUUGACAAGGCUGGGAUUUUUACUGGGAGAAGGGAUCCCAAGUGCCACACACAUAACCAUUGAAGACAAAAAUGAAACCAUGUGCACAGCUCUGAGUCAAGGCAUCAGUCCUUGCUCCACACUAACAAGCAGCACCGCAUCUCCUAGCACCGAUAGCCCCUGCUCAACCUUGAAUAGCUGUGUCAGCAAGACGGCAGCCAACAAAAGUCCCUGUGAGACCAUUAGCAGCCCUAGUUCCACCCUGGAAAGCAAGGACAGUGGAAUUAUAGCCACAAUUACAAGUUCAUCCGAAAAUGAUGACCGGAGUGGCUCCAGUUUGGAAUGGAAUAAAGAUGGAAACCUAAGAUUAGGGGUUCAGAAGGGAGUGCUUCAUGACCGCAGGGCAGAUAACUGCUCCCCAGUGGCAGAAGAGGAGACCACCGGGUCAGCAGAGAGCACGCUGCCCAAAGCAGAAUCCUCAGCUGGAGAUGGUCCAGUCCCUUAUUCUCAGGGCUCCAGCUCACUAAUAAUGCCACGGCCCAACUCAGUUGCAGCAACAAGCUCAACCAAAUUGGAAGAUCUGAGUUAUUUAGACGGGCAGAGAAAUGCUCCUCUACGGACGUCAAUUAGAUUACCAUGGCACAAUACGGCCGGAGGUAGGGCACAGGAAGUUAAAGCACGAUUUGCUCCCUACAAGCCACAAGACAUUUUGUUGAAACCCUUGUUGUUUGAAGUACCAAGCAUAACAACAGACUCUGUGUUUGUGGGAAGGGAUUGGCUCUUUCACCAGAUAGAAGAAAACUUGAGGAACACAGAACUGGCAGAAAACAGAGGCGCGGUGGUGGUUGGCAAUGUGGGAUUUGGGAAGACGGCAAUCAUUUCCAAGUUGGUGGCCCUGAGCUGCCACGGAAGCCGCAUGAGGCAGAUUGCUUCCAACAGCCCGGGUUCAUCACCUAAAACCUCUGACCCCACUCAGGAUCUUCAUUUCACUCCGUUGCUUUCACCGAGUUCUUCCACAAGUGCUUCCAGCACAGCUAAAACACCUCUUGGGUCUAUCAGUGCUGAAAACCAGAGACCAAGAGAGGAUGCAGUGAAAUAUCUUGCUUCUAAGGUGGUGGCCUACCACUACUGCCAGGCUGACAACACGUACACUUGCCUGGUGCCCGAGUUUGUGCACAGCAUCGCAGCUUUGCUCUGCCGGUCCCAUCAGCUGGCCGCCUACAGAGACCUUCUGAUAAAGGAGCCCCAACUACAGAGCAUGCUGAGCCUCCGAUCCUGUGUGCAGGACCCGGUGGCAGCUUUCAAGAGGGGAGUGCUGGAGCCACUCACAAACCUGAGAAAUGAGCAGAAAAUUCCUGAAGAAGAAUACAUUAUUUUGAUAGAUGGCUUAAAUGAAGCUGAGUUUCAUAAACCUGAUUAUGGAGAUACGCUUUCUUCAUUUAUUACCAAAAUUAUUUCUAAAUUUCCUGCCUGGUUGAAGUUGAUUGUGACUGUAAGAGCAAAUUUUCAGGAAAUCAUAAGUGCGCUGCCAUUUGUCAAGCUUUCCUUAGAUGACUUCCCAGACAACAAAGACAUCCACAGUGACCUGCACGCCUACGUCCAGCACAGGGUGCACAGCAGCCAGGACAUCCUCAGCAACAUCUCCCUGAAUGGCAAGGCCGAUGCCACACUCAUUGGAAAAGUGAGCAGCCACCUGGUGCUGCGGAGCCUCGGCUCCUACCUGUACCUCAAGCUCACCCUGGACCUUUUCCAGAGGGGCCACUUGGUCAUUAAGAGUGCCAGCUACAAGGUGGUGCCCGUGUCUCUCUCUGAGCUCUAUUUGCUUCAGUGCAACAUGAAGUUCAUGACCCAGUCCGCCUUUGAGAGGGCACUUCCGAUUCUCAACGUGGCCCUCGCAUCCCUCCACCCCAUGACAGACGAGCAGAUCUUUCAGGCUAUUAAUGCUGGCCACAUCCAGGGGGAGCAGGGAUGGGAAGACUUUCAGCAGAGGAUGGACGCCCUCUCCUGCUUCCUCAUUAAGAGGCGAGACAAAACCCGCAUGUUCUGCCACCCGUCCUUCAGGGAGUGGCUUGUAUGGAGAGCAGACGGGGAAAACACGGCCUUCCUGUGUGAGCCCAGGAACGGGCACGCGCUCUUGGCAUUCAUGUUCUCGCGUCAGGAGGGCAAGUUGAACCGCCAGCAGACCAUGGAGCUUGGCCACCACAUCCUGAAGGCGCACAUUUUCAAGGGCCUCAGUAAGAAGACGGGAAUUUCUUCAAGCCAUCUCCAAGCCCUGUGGAUCGGCUACAGCACCGAGGGGCUGUCCGCCGCCCUGGCCUCUCUCAGGAAUCUCUAUACUCCCAACGUGAAGGUGAGCCGUCUCCUGAUUUUGGGAGGGGCCAACGUGAACUACAGGACAGAAGUGUUAAAUAAUGCCCCAAUCCUGUGCGUCCAGUCUCACCUUGGCCACGAGGAAGUUGUCACUCUGCUCCUGGAAUUUGGUGCCUGCCUGGACGGAACGUCAGAGAACGGCAUGACUGCCCUCUGUUACGCAGCAGCUGCUGGCCACAUGAAGCUGGUGUGUCUGCUGACCAAGAAGGGAGUGAGAGUGGACCACUUGGAUAAGAAGGGCCAGUGUGCGCUUGUCCACAGUGCCCUACGGGGCCACGGUGACAUUCUCCAGUACCUGCUGACUUGUGAGUGGUCGCCGGGUCCUCCCCAGCCAGGCACCCUGAGGAAGAGCCACGCCCUGCAGCAGGCGCUGACCGCGGCGGCCAGCAUGGGCCACAGCUCGGUGGUCCAGUGCUUGCUGGGGAUGGAGAAGGAACAUGAAGUAGAAGUCAAUGGCACCGACACAUUGUGGGGAGAAACAGCCCUGACUGCCGCCGCAGGAAGAGGGAAGCUGGAGGUCUGUGAGCUGCUGCUGGGGCAUGGAGCUGCUGUGUCGCGGACAAACAGGAGAGGGGUUCCACCUUUGUUUUGUGCAGCACGCCAGGGGCAUUGGCAGAUUGUUAGACUGCUGUUGGAACGCGGCUGUGAUGUGAACCUAAGUGACAAGCAAGGCCGGACGCCCCUCAUGGUGGCUGCUUGUGAAGGGCACUUGAGCACCGUGGAAUUCCUCCUUUCAAAAGGUGCAGCCCUUUCUUCUCUAGACAAAGAGGGUCUGUCAGCAUUAAGCUGGGCUUGUCUGAAAGGUCACAGGGCAGUGGUCCAGUAUCUGGUUGAAGAAGGAGCUGCAAUAGACCAGACAGACAAGAAUGGCCGCACACCCUUGGACCUGGCUGCCUUCUAUGGCGAUGCCGAGACUGUGCUGUACCUGGUGGAGAAGGGAGCCGUGAUCGAGCAUGUGGACCACAGCGGGAUGCGGCCCUUGGACAGAGCCAUCGGCUGCCGGAACACAUCUGUAGUGGUGGCGCUACUCAGAAAGGGAGCCAAGUUAGGAAAUGCUGCUUGGGCGAUGGCCACUUCCAAACCUGAUAUCUUGAUUAUACUUUUACAGAAAUUAAUGGAGGAAGGAAAUGUGAUGUACAAAAAAGGGAAAAUGAAAGAGGCAGCCCAGAGGUACCAGUAUGCCUUAAGAAAGUUUCCUCGAGAAGGAUUCGGAGAGGACAUGAGACCCUUCAAUGAAUUAAGGGUUUCCCUCUAUCUCAAUUUGUCGCGAUGCCGAAGAAAAACAAAUGACUUUGGCAUGGCAGAGGAAUUUGCUUCCAAGGCUCUCGAAUUGAAGCCCAAGUCCUAUGAAGCCUUUUAUGCCAGAGCAAGAGCGAAGAGAAAUAGCAGGCAAUUCGUGGCAGCUCUGGCUGACCUGCAAGAGGCUGUGAAACUCUGUCCCACCAAUCAGGAAGUCAAGAGGCUUCUGGCCCGCGUAGAAGAGGAGUGCAAACAACUCCAGAGGAGUCAACAGCAAAAACAGCAGGGCCCGCUACCAGCUCCACUCAACGACUCCGAGAACGAAGAGGACACCCCAACCCCUGGCUUAAGUGACCACUUUCACUCUGAGGAGACUGAAGAGGAAGAAACUUCUCCCCAGGAAGAAUCUGUUUCCCCAACUCCCAGGUCCCAGCCAUCCUCAUCUGUCCCUUCCUCAUACAUCCGAAACCUUCAAGAAGGGUUACAGUCCAAAGGAAGGCCGGUAUCGCCACAGAGCAGGGCAGGAAUCGGCAAGUCCCUGAGAGAGCCUGUGGCCCAGCCAGGGCUGCUCCUGCAGCCCUCCAAGCAGGCCCAGAUCGUGAAAACCAGCCAGCACCUGGGCUCUGGCCAGUCGGCAGUGAGAAAUGGCAGUAUGAAAGUUCAGAUCUCUUCUCAGAACCCUCCUCCAAGUCCCAUGCCAGGGAGAAUCGCUGCCACUCCUGCUGGGAGCAGAACCCAGCAUUUAGAGGGAACAGGUACUUUCACUACAAGAGCUGGUUGUGGCCACUUUGGGGAUCGGCUGGGCCCCAGCCAGAAUGUCCGCCUGCAGUGUGGUGAGAAUGGCCCUGCACACCCUUUACCAAGUAAGACGAAAACCACAGAGAGGCUUCUGUCUCAUUCCUCCGUGGCUGUGGACGCAGCCCCUCCAAACCAAGGUGGGCUGGCGACCUGCAGCGACGUGCGACACCCAGCUUCCCUCACCAGCUCAGGCUCUUCUGGUUCUCCAUCCAGCAGCAUAAAGAUGUCAAGUUCAACCAGUAGUUUGACUUCGAGCAGCAGUUUUUCAGAUGGCUUCAAGGUCCAAGGACCAGAUACUAGAAUUAAAGACAAGGUUGUAACCCACGUUCAGAGCGGUACAGCUGAGCACAGACCCCGCAACACGCCGUUCAUGGGCAUCAUGGAUAAGACUGCGAGGUUCCAACAGCAGAGCAAUCCUCCAAGCCGCAGCUGGCACUGUCCGGCACCAGAGGGGCUGCUGACAAACACGUCUUCUGCAGCUGGCCUGCAGUCUGCUAACACUGAGAAGCCCUCUCUCAUGCAAGUGGGAGGAUAUAAUAACCAAGCCAAAACCUGUUCUGUUUCUACCCUGAGUGCAAGUGUCCACAAUGGGGCACAAGUGAAGGAGCUAGAAGAAAGCAAGUGCCAAAUUCCAGUCCACUCUCAAGAGAACAGGAUAACUAAGACUGUUUCUCAUCUGUACCAGGAAAGUAUCUCCAAACAGCAGCCUCAUAUUAGUAAUGAAGCCCACAGGAGCCACCUCACUGCAGCCAAACCAAAGCGAUCAUUUAUAGAGUCAAAUGUGUGAACCUUAAGAAAUCCCCAUUUGUGGAAUUUGGAAACGUGUGUUGACUCCUGGUGGUAAAUUAAAUAGUUUUUUUCAUCAGAAAAAUUAUUUUUUAGCCAUUUUUUUUCUUUGGGGUGGAUCUGAUGCCAUUGAUAUAUCUAAAAUGUGGGAUAAAACUUCUUUAAUAGCUAGAAAUCACCAUAAAUAAGAAUGCUAAACAGAAUUGAAAAUUAUAUCAACUUAAAAUUUUAAGACAGCCCAGAAGACAUUAAUGACUCUCACUUAUGAAAUUGUUUGGCUUUUGCCACUUUCUUCCUUGCCUUUGCUAUAUGGUAGAAUCACAGAACUUACUUAGAGAAUAAAUAUGUCUAUUGUUCAAGAGUAACAGGUUUAACUCAUGACCAAGUGAUGUACAUCCAAGUGAUGUAUUCUGGAAACGAUGGAAUUUUACAGUUACAGUUCCAUUGAGUCAAAUCCCAUUUUAUAUAUACAUAAAAAUUAAGUUCUGAGUGAGUUCUAGCUAAAUAUAAGUGCGACUGUAAACGCAGCCAAUUUUUUUAAGCAGAAUAUGAGAACACCUAAGUAUUCUCUUCAUAGCAGUUCCUAUAAAGGGAUUAAACACUUAUUUCUGUGUUAUGGUUCUUAUUCAUAUAUUUUUAUAGCACUUUUGGAACCUAUAUUUGUGCUUGAAGGUGUUUUUGAUAUUUGGAAACAGUAUAAGCCAUUUGGAGUCAUGAUUGGUGGUCAAGUGGAUUCAAGCUAAAAUACUAAGACCAGCAUUCUUAGUGGCGCUUAUAAAUUAGCUCUCACCUGGUUUCCAAACUGCUUUUAACAAUGGUAGUGCUCCUGGAACAAUCCUUCCAAGCUCCUCUAAGGACAAUAUUUAAUUCAGAUACUAAAGGUAAGACUGGUUGUUACUUUUGUUUUGUUGUACAAUUAGUACUUUAUAGUCACAUGUUGUAUAUAUUAAAUAGCCCAGUUUUAUUCAGACUUGUAAAUAGAACUAUUUCAAUGUAGUUAAUCUAAAAACAAAAAAGAAAACCCCAGUCACGAUUUGCAUGUUCUCUGUAAGCUUCAUCCAUGCUGGUUAUUGCACUGAAUGAUAUAUUAUUAGGGCAUGUUAACAGUAUACCAGUAACAGCACUUUAUCUCAUUUAUAUGAACACCUUUGAGGUGCUACUUAAGUCCAAGCUCUGAUGUAUUAUUCAUUUGUAAAGAUAAGGUACAGGAAUGAACCUUGGUUUAAAGGUAUUUUUAUAUGAAAAUGGUGUGUUAUUGGAAGAUGUUAAAAUGCUAAUUUGAGAGAAGUAGGAGUGUAUCUGUUUUAUAUGUUGGGAUGUGAAAUUUAUUUUCUAAAAUUGAGGAGAAGGAAGUUAUAUAUUUGCAGAAUGUUUUAAAGUGAAUUGUUGUAAUGAAGUUCCUGUGAACAUCAUUAUGGUUUUGUACAAAUAGGAACCUCUGAUGUCAUUCUUCAACGUUUGUUCCUGUGUGUACAAUUGUACUUUGUAUGAACAGCUUUAUCAUUUUUAUAGGCUUUCCAUGAGUUUUGCUGUAACUACUAUGGCUUAUUUAUUUUCUUUAAUAUUUGUGAAAGUCUUACUCCUUUGUUAGUUUUGUUUCUGCACAACUACUGUACUUUUCCAUAUGGAAUAAAGACUAUUAAUAGAA